GCCGCACCCCGAGGCCCGGCUAGGCCCUUCAGCACCAGGCGUGGGAGGCUGCCCGCCACACAGGGGUGGUGGGUGGGGUGGGAAUGAGACCUCCAGCAGUGGGCAGCGUGUCCCUGGCCCCACAGGCCCUCUCCUUUCCUCAGCUGCCUCACCUGCCCCAGUCAAGCAGCGGGGAGCUUCCCCUGUGGCCCAGAAGGGCCUCAGAGAGGGACUCUGGGCCCCAGAGGCACCCUGAGACCUUCCCUCUAGGGCCUCAGUCCAGGAGCAGAGGUAGGAGAGUACCUUGAAAGUUGCACGGUUCUCUGCGAUUGAUCUGAUACAAGGGGCCGCCUUUGGUUUUCUUGAACCGGGGGACACCUGCUUACCAAGGGGUCCUCCAGGGCCUUAUGGGCUGGAAAAGCCACAGUGGGCUCACUUGCUCUGAGAAGGGUGGACCAGCCCACCCUGCCCCCGCGCCUACCCCGCAGAGCUGACCCCUGAACCGGGCCUCUCUGCAAACCCCCACCACCCUGGCCUCUGGGAGGAGAUGGACUUCGGGGUGGCUCACUCCUGGACAGAAAGUAGCUGGGGGAAUUUUGCCCAGGCCCAGAUGGGUUUGUCUGCCCCACACUUGGGUUUCCUCCUGGUCAACCAAGGGCAGCCUGUGUGCCCCCUCCUGCCCUCCCGCACACUCCCCUUUUGCAACUAUCCUCUGAGCACCUUCAAGUUGGCCAUGUAUUUUCAUUGUCCAGCCCACACCUCUAGGUCAGGUAGAUAUUAUCGCCCCCGUUCUACAAAGGGCAAGCUGAGACUCAGAAGGCUGACUGCCCGGCCGCCCCGUGGGAGUGGCACAGCUGAGACUGCAGCCAAGCCUGUGUCUGUCCCUGUUCCAGAGCUAGCCGCUUUCCCAGGCCUCAGUCCCCUCCCCUCAGGCCAAGAGCCCCUCACACAGGUUCCAGCUGGCUGUGCAUGGUUCUGGCGCCUAUCGAAGCAAUUGAGGAACAAUUUGCCGUCUAUACUACAGAGGUUCAAGGCCAGGGAGCUUCGGAGGGGAUGCAGGGGGCAGAGGGACUGCAGGGAGACAGAGACUGGGCCGAGGCAGAGCUGGGCACAGGUGGUACCCCAUGUCCAUGGGCUCCAACCGCACAGCGAAAAUAUCCCCCCACAAUUGUGUCUAUGCUGAAUAUGUACAUUAUUCCCUGAAAGAUACUGUACAACUAUUUACAUAGCGUUUAUGUUGGAUUAGGUAUCAUAAGUAAUCUGGAGAUGAUUUCGAGUCCAGUAAGUCCUCACUUAACAUUGUGGAUAGGUUCUUGGAAACUGUGACUUUAAGUGAAACAAUGUAUGGCAGGUCCUCAAAUAUGUCAUCUUGUUCAAUGUGGAUUCAUUAUAAAAUUGAUGAGGGGAGAAAUGGCUUUGUUAUAUAUCAUGUGCUUAAAGCCACGGUUCCCAAGAACUUACUGACGGUGUUAAGUGAGGACUUACUAUAUAUGGGAGGAUACACAUGGGUUAUAUGCAAAUACAGUGCCAUUUUAUAUCAGGAACUUGAGCAUCCUCGGAUUUUGAUAUCCAAGGGAGGUCCUGGAACCAGUUCCCAGGGAUAGGGAGGGACUGUGUACAUCCCACCUUUCCCCGGUGGCCUGAUGUUGGCCCCCUUCCUGCUGUUUCUGUCACUCUAGCUGGCUCCAGGAUUCCGUUUUACGAAAUUGCAUUUUGCCCUAAAUUGGUGGCACCUGGAGCCCAGGGGUGGCAUUCCAAAACAAGAAUUUGCCCUGGAAAACUUGCUGGCUAAAUUGUGUCUUGUAAGGCCCAAGUCAUGCCUUUGCGUGGAGGAUGUCCUGAGGCCCUAGACACAAUCCCCCCGGCCCACCCCCAACGCUCAGGGGCUUGUUGAGAACGAAGGUGGGGAAGGUGGAGGCUAACAUUUCUCUGACUGAGGGGCACACAAUCCCCACUGUCCCUGAGAGGAGCCAGCCAUCGGGACCCCAGGUGGGGGACCCAGGAGCUCAGCCUUUGCCGCCUAAGACUCUUACUCUUACACAAAUGUAAGCCCUUGUCAAGGAGGUAACGCCCCCAGGUCCCCUCGAUCCGGAGGGGACACUGCUAGGAGGCCUUUCCUGGGGUCGGGGGAGUGGGCAAGGCAGGGUCCCUCCACCACCUCCCACUGCCAAGACUCCUUCCCUCUGGGUCCCACAUCAGCCCAGGCAUGACCCAUCCCCUCAGACCCGUGUCCUGGUGGGCUCUCGGAGGGAAAUGCACUGGCGUUCUGCCUCCACCUACCCUCACCUGGGGAAGGGCACGGUGCUGAUGUGGGCAGGACAGGCCCCUGCCCUUUCCUCUGUCUGCCUCCUCCCAGUAGCCACAGCCAGGACAGGGGACAGCAGGAUGGGUGGUUCCCCGCCCCCUCCUUUUGGGGGUGUCCAUGUGAGAACCCUCAUGUGGCCCAGGACAUGGCUUGGGGCAUUUCUUGCCCACCACAGGGUAGGAAAGGACCAGCUGACUCUCUGAGGUGCCUCUGAGGCCCCAGCUGUGGCACAGGUGUGGGGUUGGAAAGCUGUAGGUGUGGAGGGGCAUGGAUACGGGGGCCAUGAGGGUGGGGUCCAGGCUGGACCAGGCCUGCCCUGAGUCCCCCAGCAGGUGCUCCAGGCUGGCUCACACCCUCUGCCUCUCUCUCUUCCUUCCUGGCCCCAACCCUUGAGGCAGCAGACUGUGCCAGGCACCAGGCAUGACAAGCCUCACUCGUCUCAGAGAUGGUGAGGGAAGGACAGGGUUGGGCCAGCCCCUGCUCCGAGCUGUCCUGAGGUGUCUUCCUUGGACCACAUGCCCCUUUCCAGGCAAAGGCCACUAUCCUGGACCUCCAGUCCCUUCCUCCUGGUCCCCCGUUCCCUCCCCACCGCACCUUCCUGCUUUUCUGGGCCGGGCCCACAGCUUCCUGGGUGAUGAAGAGCUGUGUUCUCUCCUGCCCCCACCAGCCCGAGGUCCUCCAGGCUCUGUAAAGACUUGUCCUGACUGUUUCUGCUCUCUGGGUUGUUGGUGGCUGCCCCAGUGGUGUGCAGAAGGGGAGGAGGACAGGAAGGGGCCCUGCUUGGGACUCCCCAACCCUCCUCUGUGCCCUGCAGGCUCCUCCAUGCAACUGCACCCCCACAGCCCAUUUCCUCUGCAGGGGAGGCCCCGUGAGGGCAGGAGGGGGCAGGAACCGUGUUGUGUGACCAUGGCACCUCUGGUACCUGACACAGUGUUGGGCACACAUGUGGGAACCUGCUGGCAUUCACUGAAUGAACGGUGCCCUCUGUGCCAGGCCCCCCACCAGGUGCUGGGGGUACUGUCUGUGCAAGGUGGUCCUUAUCAGGGAACAGGAGUGUGUGGGGCGUGCAGUGAUGGCGGGAGUGCAUCCUUGCCAAGGAUGGCUGAAAUGCAGUGGCGCAAUCUCGGCUCACUGCAACCUCCGCCUCCCUGGUUCAAGCAAUUAUCUUGCCUCAGUCUCCCAAGUAGCUGGGAUUACAGGUGCCCACCACCACACCCAGCUAAUUUUUGUAUUUUUAGUAGAGACGGGGUUUCACCACGUUGGCCGGGCUGCUCUCAAACUCCUGACUACAAGAGAUCUGCCUGCCUCGGCCUCCCAAAAUUCUGAGAUUACAGGCGUGAGCCCCCAUGCCCGGCCAGGACUGGUCAGUUUUAAAAUGUGGACAUUACUGGGCCUGUCCCCACACAUGUCACACCCCAGCAUGGACCCCACAGGGCACUGGGGAAGGCACCGUGGGUGCCUUCGUGUAGCCCAGAGUGAAGGGGCCGCUCGACCGGGAGGGGUUGCUGGGUGGCCAGGCUGUGCAGGCUUUUCUCUCCGGAGUCCCGGGGGACUUCCUGGCAGCCCCUGAUCCCCACUCCCCUGGC